ACUAGGAAAGAAGAAAGUAUUAGUGAAGCAAAAAAGCUGACAAAUCUUAAGUUUCUGAAAGGAAAUCAUUUUAAAGUUUUAAAUUAAAAACCAAAGACAUUCCAAAGUCUAAAGACCACAUUUUUAAGUUUUAUUGAAAAUGCUGCAUUGUUAAUAACAUCCUCUUAAGGAAAUUUUUAUUUUGGUGUUUUGGUUUUGAGAAGUAUCUGUGGCAAAACUAAUGGCAGUAUGAUAAAUGUUGCCUGUGUCAGUUAACUUUCAGAAUUUACCGUGUGUGUGAAAUACUCAUAUUCAUUAUAAAUAAAUGGAUUAAUCUCUAUGGCCCUUUGGCUACAUAAAACAAAAAAAUCUGCCAUGUGCUCAGAGUUCAGAAAAAGCUAUUCUUGUGUGGUAAUCUUUUAACAAUCAGGUUUUUAAUACUCUCCUUUAACACAAGACUGCUAAAUGAUCAGCUUCUCAAAUUAGUGUAUCAUAACGCAUGACAGAAAAUCAUUAAAUGGAAUCACUAAUGAGGAAAGGCAUUGCUGAUUUUUAUACCUUAAUCACUUGACAUUGUUCAUCUUUAUAAGAGGGCUAAAUAUUACUUACUACCUCUGACUAGGAAUACUGUUAAAUUGUAUUACUGUGCUGAUAUGCAAGAAAUUCUGUCCAAAUACAGAACUUAUUUAAAUUAUUAAAAACAUAUGGGCCAGGCAUGGUGGCUCACGCCUGUAAUCCCAGCACUUUGGGAGGCCAAGGCGGGUGGAUCACUUGAGGUCAGGAGUUUGAGACCAGCCUGGCCAACAUGGCAAAACCUCGUCUCUACUGAAAAUACAAAAAUUAGCUGGGUGUGGUGGUGCACACUUGUGGUCCCAGCUACUUGGGAGGCUGAGGCAGGAGAAUCGCUUGAACCUGGAAGGCAGAGGUUGCAGUGAGCUGAGAUCACGCCACUGCACUCCAGCCUGGGUGACAGAGCAAGACUGUCUCCAAAACAAAACAUACUAUUGUUAUCACUGCAGUGUAACCAUGACGUCCUAUUAUUAUUUUAUUUUUCAAAAUCAAGAAAUGCAAGUGGCGCCAUUCUUCUUGAGUGGCUAUUUGAUCAUAUAAAAAUCACUUCCUGCCAGUUUAUGAUCUCUAUUGCACUGUAACUUAUUUGUAAAGUAGAUGGAAACAUUUUAGAUUAAAUUAUGAAGUAAUUUUCCCUUAUAUAGGCUGCUUUCUUGCUGUCUUUAGGGAUCCCUAAUAAAAUCAGCUAUGAGGACAACAAGGUGAAGAAUGAAACCAAUUUACCUUCACAAUCAUCUAAAGUCCAACAUGUUUACCGUGGCUGAUGUGUUGAGUCAAGAUGAACUGCGCAAAAAGCUAUACCAGACGUUUAAGGAUCGGGGUAUACUGGAUACACUCAAGACACAACUUCGAAACCAGCUAAUUCAUGAGUUGAUGCACCCUGUAUUGAGUGGAGAACUGCAGCCUCGGUCCAUUUCAGUAGAAGGGAGCUCCCUCUUAAUAGGCGCCUCUAACUCUUUAGUGGCAGAUCACUUACAAAGAUGUGGCUAUGAAUAUUCACUUUCUGUUUUCUUUCCAGAAAGUGGUUUGGCAAAAGAAAAGGUAUUUACUAUGCAGGAUCUAUUACAACUCAUUAAAAUCAACCCUACUUCCAGUCUCUACAAAUCACUGGUUUCAGGAUCUGAUAAAGAAAAUCAAAAAGGUUUUCUUAUGCAUUUUUUAAAAGAAUUGGCAGAAUAUCAUCAAGCUAAAGAGAGUUGUAAUAUGGAAACUCAGACAAGUUCGACAUUUAACAGAGAUUCUCUGGCUGAGAAGCUUCAGCUUAUUGAUGAUCAGUUUGCAGAUGCUUACCCUCAGCGUAUCAAGUUCGAAUCUUUAGAAAUAAAGCUAAAUGAGUAUAAGAGAGAAAUAGAAGAGCAACUUCGGGCAGAAAUGUGUCAAAAGUUGAAGUUUUUUAAAGAUACCGAGAUAGCAAAAAUUAAAAUGGAAGCAAAAAAAAAGUAUGAAAAGGAGUUAACCAUGUUCCAGAAUGAUUUUGAAAAAGCUUGUCAAGCAAAAUCUGAAGCUCUCGUUCUUCGGGAAAAGAGUACCCUUGAAAGAAUUCACAAGCACCAAGAGAUUGAAACAAAAGAAAUUUAUGCUCAAAGGCAACUUUUACUAAAAGAUAUGGAUUUGCUAAGAGGAAGAGAAGCAGAGCUGAAGCAAAGAGUUGAAGCUUUUGAAUUGAACCAGAAGCUCCAGGAAGAAAAACAUAAAAGCAUAACUGAGGCACUUAGGAGACAGGAGCAGAAUAUAAAGAGUUUUGAGGAGACCUAUGACCGAAAGCUCAAGAAUGAACUUCUAAAGUAUCAACUUGAACUGAAGGAUGACUACAUCAUUAGAACUAAUCGACUGAUUGAAGAUGAAAGGAAGAAUAAAGAAAAAGCUGUUCAUUUGCAAGAGGAGCUCAUAGCUAUUAAUUCAAAAAAGGAGGAACUCAAUCAAUCUGUAAAUCGUGUGAAAGAACUUGAGCUUGAAUUAGAGUCUGUCAAAGCCCAGUCUUUGGCAAUAACAAAACAAAACCAUAUGCUGAAUGAAAAGGUUAAAGAGAUGAGUGAUUAUUCACUACUAAAAGAAGAGAAACUGGAGCUUCUGGCACAAAAUAAAUUACUUAAACAACAACUGGAAGAGAGUAGAAAUGAAAACCUGCGUCUCCUAAACCGCCUAGCUCAGCCGGCUCCUGAACUUGCAGUCUUUCAGAAAGAACUACGGAAAGCCGAAAAGGCUAUAGUGGUUGAGCAUGAGGAGUUCGAAAGCUGCAGGCAAGCUCUGCACAAACAACUGCAAGACGAAAUUGAGCAUUCUGCACAGCUGAAGGCCCAGAUUCUAGGUUACAAAGCUUCUGUAAAGAGUUUAACUACUCAGGUUGCCGAUUUAAAAUUGCAACUGAAGCAAACUCAGACAGCCCUAGAGAAUGAAGUGUACUGCAAUCCAAAGCAGUCUGUGAUCGAUCGUUCUGUCAAUGGAUUAAUAAAUGGCAAUGUGGUGCCUUGCAAUGGUGAGAUAAGUGGGGAUUUCUUGAACAAUCCUUUUAAACAGGAAAACGUUCUAGCACGUAUGGUUGCAUCAAGGAUCACAAAUUAUCCAACUGCAUGGGUGGAGGGUAGUUCCCCUGAUUCUGACCUUGAGUUUGUAGCCAAUACUAAGGCAAGGGUCAAAGAGCUUCAGCAAGAGGCCGAACGCUUGGAAAAGGCUUUCAGAAGUUACCAUCGGAGAGUCAUUAAAAACUCUGCCAAAAGCCCACUAGCAGCAAAGAGCCCACCAUCUCUGCACUUGCUGGAAGCCUUCAAAAACAUUACUUCCAGUUCCCCGGAAAGACAUAUUUUUGGAGAGGACAGAGUUGUCUCUGAGCAGCCUCAAGUGGGCACACUUGAAGAAAGGAAUGACGUCGUGGAAGCACUGACAGGCAGUGCAGCCUCGAGGCUCCGCGGGGGCACUUCCUCCAGACGCCUCUCUUCCACACCCCUUCCAAAAGCAAAAAGAAGCCUCGAAAGUGAAAUGUAUCUGGAAGGUCUGGGCAGAUCACACAUUGCUUCCCCCAGUCCUUGUCCUGACAGAAUGCCCCUACCAUCACCCACUGAGUCUAGGCACAGCCUCUCCAUCCCUCCUGUCUCCAGCCCUCCGGAGCAGAAAGUGGGUCUUUAUCGAAGACAAACUGAACUUCAAGACAAAAGUGAAUUUUCAGAUGUGGACAAGCUAGCUUUUAAGGAUAAUGAGGAGUUUGAAUCAUCUUUUGAAUCUGCAGGGAACAUGCCAAGGCAGUUGGAAAUGGGCGGGCUUUCUCCUGCCGGGGAUAUGUCUCAUGUGGACGCUGCUGCAGCUGCUGUGCCCCUCUCAUAUCAGCACCCAAGUGUAGAUCAGAAACAAAUUGAAGAACAAAAGGAAGAAGAAAAAAUACGGGAACAGCAAGUGAAAGAACGAAGGCAGAGAGAAGAAAGAAGGCAGAGUAACCUACAAGAAGUUUUAGAAAGGGAACGAAGAGAACUAGAAAAACUGUAUCAGGAAAGGAAGAUGAUUGAAGAAUCACUGAAGAUUAAAAUAAAAAAGGAAUUAGAAAUGGAAAAUGAAUUAGAAAUGAGUAAUCAAGAAAUAAAAGACAAAUCUGCUCACAGUGAAAAUCCUUUAGAGAAAUACAUGAAAAUCAUCCAGCAGGAGCAAGACCAGGAGUCGGCAGAUAAGAGCUCAAAAAAGAUGGUCCAAGAAGGCUCCCUAGUGGACACGCUGCAAUCUAGUGACAAAGUCGAAAGGUGACUAAGAGUGGGAUUAGUGACCUUAUAAAAGGGCUCAAUGGAACUAGCUAGGCCCUUUUGCCCUUGCACCAUUUGAAGACACUGCAUUGAUCCCCUCUGGAGAACACAGCAACAAGGCACCAUCUUGGAAGCCGAGACCGGGCCUUCACCAGACAUCGAACCUGCCAGUGCCUUCCUUGAUCUUCGACUUCCCAGCCUCUAAAACUGUAAGAAAUACAUUUCUGGUCUUUGUAAGUUACCCAGUCUAAGGUAUUUUGCUAUAGCAGCAGGAACAGACUGAGAUAGCAUCUUUAUUAUGGAACCUUUGGUCCUCAUACUUAAUGAAUGGGCGUAUUUCCUUUGUUUUUAAAUGAAUGGGCUCCUUCCCUAUAAUUGACUUCAUCUCUUAAAAAAUCAAGUUUUACAAGGCAGAACUGGAAAAAAAUCUCUACUGAACCCUCUAAAGGGUCCUAGGUUUCGUGGCAGGAUCACUAUGGGUAAUUAAGAGGCUGCUUGUGAUUUUAUCUAACCAUUAUUUACAGUUUUCCUCUGGUGACUCAUGUGACUUAAAUAAUUGCACAAAAUGCUACUUAAACAGAAGAUACUAAGUAGUGUGACAAAUAGCACACUAAUUGAGCCUCCUGAUUGUUCUGCCAUGCAUGAAGGAAGGGUGAUGAUCUAGAGUCAGCACCUCAUUUAGGAAUGGCCAUGUGUCAAUAGUGACAAAGGCUGGGCCUCACUAAGAAAGGUCAGACGCAGAGAAUCCAAAUGCAUAAUCAUGUUGAGAGGUAAGAGUUUAAACAGAUUAUAAAAUAAAAUCCUAAGUAACAUAUUUAGCUUGGCUACUCUAGAGAGUCAACUGUUAGAACUAGGUUUUUUUGUAUUCCAGAGUAAAUCUUUCAAUAGACUUUUGUACCUUUGGUUUGAAAAAUAACUACACACAUGCCCUUAUUUUGUUUCUGCUUUGCCCACGUUUAAGCUUUGUUGAUCCUAUAGGUAGAUGGCAUUUAUUUGUUGAAAAACUAGUCAGAAAAAUUCUUACUUUAUAGAGAACUACAGACGUGCUAGUGGCACUUUUAUGCCCAAUACAGCCCAGUGGAUUAUUUAAUAUUUUCUUUAAUUGCUGAAGAGAUUUUUGCCAGAAAUAAAACAAUUAGCACUCACAGAUUUGAUUUCCAUACCAAUGUGAAAUCUUGACUCUGCACAUUAUUCAAAAGUGAAACCAUACUGAGAACAAAGAAAGAUAGGAUUUAUGUAUGGUAAAAAGGCAAGUGAAUGAAGCUAUAAUUUUAUUUCAUUACUCUUAGUACAUCCACAACUAUUUCCACCUAAAUAGAUCUUUAAAAUAAGCAUACACAAGUAUUGACUAUUAUCUACAAAUAUUUAUUGUAACACUUGAAUAGAACUACAGGAAGCCCUUGGCACUGAUAGAAAAUAUUGAUUCACUGUUAGGUUACAAAAAUUUAUACAUAGCAAAAUUUAAUGCUCUUUACAUAAAAAAUAUUAGACUACUUAAACAAAACUUUCAAAAAUUCCUGGUAAUAGCUACCAGAAUUAGAAAAGUAAAAUUAGGCUUUAGACACUGCCUCUUCUAGAACACUGGACUCUGACAGCACCUCCACUGCUGGAAAGAAUAGUUAAAUCUGUCAUGCAACAGGAAAACAAAACACUAAGCUAUUUUGGAACAACUGUUCUACACAGAAGAGAGCUUCUCUUAAUUUAAAAAAAAAAAAAAAUCCCAAAUAGGCAUUUUUAGGCAUUAACCAAAAAAGAGAAUCCAAAUGAAAUAUUAUACUUGAUGUUCAAUUUUAAUAGCAUCUUGAUAAAGGUAUGCUUCCUUUCAUUUGAAUACAUUUCUGCACAUGUAUGUUAUAAAAUCCAGGAAACAGCCAAACCACAAGUUAACUCUUAACAAUGAAUAUACAUAGUUAACCCUAUAGUAAGCAGCCCCUUUGAAAAGCACUGAUGCACCCAACAGUUAUAUGGAUCAUUUCAUAAAGAGCAACACAAAGUUUACCAUCACUAAUACCCAGUACCUACAGUCACUUAAUGUUCUGGAACACAAUAAUGUAAAAGGCAAGUUUCUUUUGAAAAUGGCUUAAACUCAAGCAGUUCUCUUGCUGAACAUCAAACUUUAUUAUUCCAGGAAACUAAGAUUUAGAUAAGAAAAAAAUGAAAUACCAACCCUAAUUUAAAUUACUUAAGUAUUCAAGUCUAUAAAAGUAGGAGGUUAGAGGUCUGUGGUCAAUUUGCAAUUAGGUUUUAGAUAGUUGGUAUGAAACUGUAAACUUCGUAUCCAGACCACUGAAAAAUGGUUUAGAAUGGUGGUCAUUUUAAUAAGGUAACACUUCUUAAUAAUUAAGAAAAACAUUUAUGGAACAAAAUUCUGUGAAAGAUAUUUGGGUCUCUAGUUAUGAUAUAAAUUCUUAGAAAUUUAAAGCAAAUACUCAUUAAGGCAAAGCUGACAUUUCUCAAGAAUAAUGAAAAUUGGAUCAGUAUUUUGUUAAAAUGAAAUCUGUUAUAAAAUUGCUUCUGGAAAGCUUGUCAGUGAGUCCAGCAUCCAGAUUCUUUAAUAGUAGGGUCAGCAGAAUUGUAGCUAAUUUUAGCAUUAUUGAAAAAUAUAUUUCUGAUUGGCUCAGGAAAUUAAUGGGUCCUGGACUUGGGAGGGAAAAGCUAGUUUGAGAAAUCAAUCAUAAGAAUCACAUUAUCUUUGAUCCAAAGUUUAAUAAAUGUCAGCUGUCAGAAAUGGAACUUUACAUCAAUUCCAUUUUAUUUCCUAUGUAGAUAACACUUGAGGACAGAUGGCAUAUAUGUGAAUUUACGGUCUUAUCCCUUGAUGCUGGGCAUGUCACAGGUCCUUAUUAAGGAGUCACAGGUCCCUAUUAAGGAGUGUGACAUAUUCCAUUGAGUGUCUUGGUAGAAUUGCCCUAGCAAUAAAUGUGAACAUGCCACAAAUUCCCAAAGUAUGAACGAUCAUUUUGUCAAAGUGUUGCCUUUUAAAAUGGCUAACAUGAAACCUCCAAUAUUUGUUCUAAAGAAAAAGAUUUACCCACUGGAAGGUUUUCCUAGAGAUACAUCCCAGCAGCUUGAGACAGACAGUGAAGUGUUUGUACAUCUACAUUAGUUUGGUGGGAUACACAUCUGUACUGCAGAGCAGCUGUCUGAUGAUUUGUCAGAGCUGUAAAUACGUCGGCCGAAACACUCUGGCAAACAUUUAUGUGUAAGAAUUGAGUUGUUCUUUUGACCGAGACUGGAUAUCUUGCAGUUCCUGUUCUUCCUUUGCUUUGAUAUCCUGGUAAGCCUGCAUUUUGCUCGCAUCCUUUAAGUAAGCCCAGUUAGAAGACAGUAUCAUGAGGAAGUGGAUCUGGAAGAGAAGGGUGAGCAUGAUGGCUAGUGAGCAUUGUGAGAAGGCAAAGCGAGGCGCUAGUUAGAUUAGACAGACUUGACUUUAAAGGGGCGAAGGUUAAUUCUGUAUUAAUAAAUACUCGCUCUACUAGCAGAGCUGUCAGAUCCUGAAAGCAUGCUCUACUAGUUGGCUUCGCAUUAAAAGGCUGAAGAAAAGUUAGUAUACAAACAUAGUGAACUGGAAAAAAAUGGCCAAAGGUAUUGUUAAGAAAAAGCAAAAAUGAAAUACGAGAGGGUGCUUUUUUUUUUUUUUUUAAUACCAUUUUGAGAGUAAUUUUAAAGACUAAUGCGAAAGUUCGGGAGCACAUUGUAUAUUUGAAAUAAGUGUAGUGUGUGCAAAGACCAUUUUCUACCUGUGGAUAAAAAUCAAUUCCCCCAAAGGCCUAAAAGCAUGAACAAUGUUUAUUUUGAGUAAAUAAUUAAACUACAUAUUUAACAUGGAAAAAAUUAAAUGAAUGUCAAAACCAAAAUUAAGAACUAUAAGCAAAGCAUGCAGUCUCUGUUAACAAAACUUAGUUGUGAAACUACAUUUUUCAUUUUGUAAAUGCCAUUAUUUCAUUUCAUAAAAUGUAAAAAUCCUCAGUAUCAUUCUUUACACUUGAUGCGGCAAACACUUCUUUCCUAUUUUCCUCGUAUUUCCUGCAAAAUAAAUCUACAUCUCAAGUUC